GUGCCAGGCCAGGUGCUCCCUGCAGGGCAGGAGCUCCCGCGAUGAUAGUGACCUCUGGGAGAAGACGCACACCUUCCCACGGGGGCUCCUCCCCAGCCAGAGCUACACUUGGCAAACCUUUGGUCCUAAAUGAUUUAUUCUCUGAAUUGAAGAAAUACGGUUUACAUAUCUUCUAAGUAUAUAUGUAGGUAGCAAUAUAUAUAUUUAUUUCUAUGAACUAACACCUACCCUUAGUAUGCAUGAUUCACUCUGAUAUCCUAGUCUACUUCCAUUCCAGUCUUUGUGUUCUGUUGAAAGAAUUUUUUUAAAAAACAUAAUUCCUCUCCCACUCUGUUGGUUUCAGGUUGUUAUUAGCAGAACUCUGGAGCCAUGCUGCCUUAACAAACCCAAUUUUCCUGGUGGACACUGCUAUUACCUAGGGCUCUUGGCAUCGUGUUUUCAGGGGCUGCCUCAGAUUGUGCAAUGAAGUGAAGUGGAAAAUUCAAAACUUUUAUUCUACCCAUUCUUUCAUCUGCCGUCUAGGCAGGCUACAAACCUCCCCAACAUCUCUGCCGCUAACCCCCUCCAACAGACACUGCAAGUGUCACACACAAGUACCAGCUCAACACAGUCUCCAGUCUCACUCUGGGCUUUCCCUGUUUUGUUGUGUAGAUUUUCUUGCUGAUACUGGUGUUUUACUUUCUGUUUCCAUUCUAUAAAUUUACAGGGUUGAUUUGGGAAGCAGAGCACAGCAGCCCAAAUUUGCUUGUAAUGUCGGCGGCUACAGAGGAAAGGCCAAGAAUGGACAGAUUAAUAAAGGGCCAUCUACAAGCCACGAAUAAGGCCAUCACCAGAAGCCAACCCCGCCAGUCCUUGAUCUAGGACUUCCAGACUUCAAAACUGUGAGAAAAAAAAUAAAUUUCUGUUGUUUUAGCUACUCACUCAAUGGCAUUUUGUUAUGGCAGCCUGAGCUGACUUAAGACAUAACUUCAGGUGACACAAUUUUUUUUUUGUUUCCUCCUAGAAAAAAAAAAAGUAAUUUUGACAUUUAAAGUCUGUAGUUCAUUUUGAGUUACAUUUCUGUAUGGUGCAAGAUAUGUGCAAUGGCUAGUACUAUGUGUCAACUUGUCUAGGCUAUACUGCUCAGCUGUGUGGUCAAACAGUAGUCUAGAUGUUGCUGUGAAGGUAUUUUGUAGAUGUGAUCAACAUUUACAAUCAGUUGAUUUUAAGUAAAGCAGUUUAACUUCCAUAAUGUGGAUGGGCCUCAUCCAAUUAGUUGAAGGUGUUAAGAGAAAAGACCAAGGUUUCCUGGAAAAGGAAUUCUACCACAAGACUAACAUAAAAAUGCGCUGUGAGUUUCUAGCCUGCUGGCCUGCCUUCACUGUCCUGGGGGAGGCUUGGAGAGACCAGGUGGACUGGAGUAGACUGUUGAGAGACGCUGGUCUGGUGAAGAUGUCCAGGAAACCACGAGCCUCCAGCCCAUUGUCCAACAACCACCCACCAACACCAAAGAGGCGAGGAAGUGGAAGGCAUCCUCUCAACCCUGGCCCAGAAGCCCUAUCAAAGUUCCCAAGACAACCCGGAAGGGAAAAGGGACCCAUCAAGGAAGUUCCAGGAACAAAAGGCUCUCCCUAAAAGACCGCCGCUUCAAAAAAACCUGAGGAAUGGAGUGGGCCAACACUAUCCAGCCACUCUGACCAGCCGAACGAGGAACUCAAUCAAAAUGAGCCAUAGCGGGACCACAAGGGCAAGGAGACCACCACCUUCUCCAGUCUCUCUUCGGACAGCCAGUAAUUCCCGGGCAAGGCCAGAGACUUCAAGUCUAUCUGAAAAGUCUCCAGAGGUCUAACCCCAGAUAAAUAGCCAACAGGGUGUAGAGUACAUUUUACACCCCAAAGAGUGUGCCCCAUGGUGAUGAAAAUAAAGUGAACAUGUUGCAAAA